CCAUAUUCUGGUCCUAAGGAUUUAUUUCUUAAGUUAACAAUAUAGUGAGAUCACUGAAAGUCUUUCUUCAGAUUUACAGAGUAAAAUUUUCUUUGAUGAAUCUGACAUAAAUGCUGGUAAAUUUUUAUAGUUGGUCAACUCGAAUUGGUAUUAAUUCUUCUCAUAGCUUGCUUUUUUUCUUUUGAAAUUUACAUUAGGAGAAGUACCUCUUGAGAAGUAUUCUAAGCAGAACAUGUAUUUUAAAAUGUGUUUUAAGAAGGAAAACAUUGAAAUGCAUUCUAAAUAGAAUUAGGUAUUUUAACAAUCAUUGUGUGACAGUUUUAGAUGUAGCAAAGUAUCUGCUACUUCAGGUUUGAAUUGCUUUUAAUCAGAAAAUGCUGUUAAUGAGUUAUGUUCAAUCUAGGAAGAUAGGCUUGUCAUUUGUAACUAAUGUACUGAAAAAAACACUAGAUAUGAAAAAGACCCCUGCCCUCUUCAAAUAGCAUUACCUGUGGUAUGAUUUAUUUUAGUUCUGCCUUCGAGGAUUUUUUUUUCCUUGUGAAAUUUUUUGCUGGCCUGUAUCAGUAGAUUUGCAGAGACGGGGAGUAAUCCAUUUGUGCUUCUCCCCCUGCCCCACGACCACAAUUGUUGGCUUUUAACAUAUGUCAUCUUAGGCCUCCUCCAUAUUAGUUUAUGAUUAGUGUCUGUAAUGGACACUGUCAGUCCAUUGACUCUUGGUCUGAUUGGAGAAUUCUUACCCUGGCAGGCAGAUCUUCUCAGACACACUCGCCUGAGACUGUGAACCUGAGGCUGGAGGCAAGGAAAGAAGAGUAGCCCAUGUGGCCAUUUUCUGGGGGGAUGCACAGUGGUGGCUGCUGUGCUGCUUCUAGAGGCAAGGUCUAGUUGUUGCUGCAAUGAUGAUGCAGUCUGCUGUGUCCCCUUAGGCAUUGUUAUGGCCAGGGGGAGAUUCUGUGAACUGUCUAAUAGCCGCCUCCCCUUUUUUUAAAUCACUUUUCUGUUUAAAUUACCUAGAAUUAGUUUCUGAUGCUCUCAACUAAGAAUUCUGAUACUUCAGCAUCCAGACUUGUCACUGUCGCUGGUCAGAUACGUGGUAGAAGCCCUUGUGAAGAGCAGUGAUGUAUCUUUUUCAUCCUGGCUGCCUGUACAUUCUGGUCAGAGGUGACCCAGAGGACUGGAGGAGGACACAGUCGAUAUCAGCUGUGGGUCGUGGGAGCUGUGUUUGCUGGUGGUCAGGCAGGACUCCCGAACCACACACUAGCCCAGCCCACUGGGUCUCAUCAUGUGCCACUCUUUACUGCUGCUUUUUCCUAAUUCUUUGUCCCCCAAAAGUUGGGAUGCCUAGGAGCUAAUACAUAACUCCUUGUGCAUUUUUUUUUUGGCUCUGAUGUGGGAAUAUUAGCUACAGAAAUAUGUGUGUGUGUGCGUGCGUGUGUGUGUGUGCGUGUUUUAGUGGAAUGUUUAUUUUGUUUAGCCAAAAAUUACAUCUGAUGUACCAAAUACCUUUUUAGUCAACAUUAUUUAGGUAUAAUUUCACGUAUUAUAAAAUUAUACUCAUUUUAAGUGUUGUUGGGUGAAUUUACUAAAGAUAUAGAACAUUUCAUUACCCCAAAAGUUCCCUUGUGUCCCCUUGUAGUCAGUGCUUCUCCUCCUGCCCCACUACCACAAUUGUUGGCUUUUAACAUAUGUUACCUUAGGCCUCCUCCAUAUUAGCUGAUGAUUUGUCACUUUGCUGUUCCUGAGGAUAUUACAGUAUAAUAAAGGCAUGAUAAAUCUCUCGUUUUUACUGAACUAUGAAAUCCAAAGAAAAACUAUCAGUGCUGUAUAAAUUAUCAGUCUGAUAAAUAAUACUUUGCCGCACAGAAGUGUCUUGAGUUAGAUGACUUGUUCUGGUGAGCGGCUUUCCAGUGGAUGGCUUUUCUGGCUUCUCUGUGGCCUGUAGACAUGCAGGGCUCGGGUUUUCUCCCUGGAUGUGAUGAUGUCUUUUAAUUGUUAUCUGGGUCAGGUUGGGAGGCAAGAAAGCCAAAAUGGCUGAAUUCAAAUCCUUGCUCUGUCAUCUCCUAGCCAAGGGACUGGAGUAGAGUUACCCAGCUGCUCUGUGUGCGCUUCAGAGCCCUCAUGCCUAAAAAUUGCCUGUUGAAGGCUGUUCAGUCACCAAGUGUUUAUUGGGUAUCUACUAUGUACCAGGCCCUGCUCUUCAUAUUUCAUGAAGUUUUCCUUUUAGUGUAGGGGAGGGGGCAGAUAGUAACAAGUAAAUUGUGUAAUACGUCAGAUGGUGAUAGGUUCUGUAGAGAAAAACAGCAGGGAAGGGGUGCAUGCAGGCACCCCUGUGUGCGGGCGUGGGGUGGGGUGGAGGGUGUUGUAAUUUUAAAUAGUGGAGCCAGGAAAGGCUUCACUAAGGAGGUUUUAAGCUAAGCCCUGAUGGAGCUGAGGGGCCAUUCCAGGCAGAGAGAAUACAAAUGCAGAAGCUCAGAGUGGGGAGCAGGCCUAUAUUUGAGGAACAGCAGAGGCUGGGGUGCUUAGAGUUGUGGGGGAGGGCAGAGGGAAGAAAGUAGGAGGCAAAAAUCAUAAGUGGUCCAAAGGAUUAAAUGAGAUGAAACACGUAAAGUGUUUUUGAUGCUUACAAUUACUGUGUGAUGACAGUCUCCUAGGUAGCCUUUAAAAAAUCACUCUUGAGAAGAAAAGUUAUAAGAAAGAACAGAACCAAAUGAGGCAUUCCCUCACUCAGCCAUUCAGCAAACAUUCAAGGGGAUUUUUGCUGCCAGGUGCUGCUGUCACAGGCAGGACUGUGUGGGGGAGACCGGGGCUUCAGGAGCUUCCUUCAGUGAGUUCAUUGUGGAGACAGAAGGAAUGGAUGCAUGGGACGAUGAUGCCUGCUAGGUUAGAUGGAUGCCCCGGGGGCUUUGAGAACAUGUGGGGAAUGGUUAGCAGUUGUCAUGUGAGUUUUAGCUUUUGAAGUUGGAUUAUGUGAAGAACAGGAUGUGUAUGCAUGUGCAGGUGGCAUAUGGGGUCAGGUGGGAGCUUUCCAAGCCCAGCGACAACAUGGCAUGGUGGGGACAGAGAACUGUGGCAGGAGAGUGGGUGUUUGGUAGGCUAGAGUGGAGGGGAAGGUGAGGUGCAGGGCUAGGCAGGAGCUGGUGGCAGGGGUGGGGUGGGGUCGGUGGGAAGAACUCAAAAGAGGCACCAGGGAGAGUGUAUGAGUGGAAAGGAACUGAGAGAAGGAAAGAGAAGUCCCAGGUGGGGCACAGGGAGGGAGGAGGAGCAAAGGGGAAUGGGGAGGGACUAACACGAAUUCAGUGAUGAUCUUGGAUUUGCUUCAACUGCUUUGCCUGCAUUAACUCAUUUAAUCCUCACAGCAACCCUCAAUAAGUUAGGGACUGUUAUUAUCUCUGUUUCACAGAUGAGGACGCUGAGGUGUAGAAAGGUUAACUCCCCUUCUCAAGGUCACACAGCUUAUAAGUGGUGAAUUGAGAUUCUAACUCAAGCAUUCUGACUCCAUGGUCUUGGUAACCCUCUACUGCCACUGAAAUCAUUCUUAACAUUUUGUUUGUGCUUUUCAUUGAACCCUGAUUGGAACACUGCAUGUAUAUUGGAAUUCUUUUUUUUUCUUUUGUCACUGGCCUAUGAAUGAUGCUGACAGAGCCAGCUGAUGGAUUAUCUCUUGGUUCUUUUCUUCUUGGAAUGAGUCCCAGCAGGAUCAGGAUCUGGGAUUUCUGAGUCUCUUCUUUCCCAUUCUUCUUCAUCCCCUCUCAUUUUUGCUGGUUUGCUUACAAUGAGAGUAGACAUUUAAAAACUGAUUUUAAGUGGGAAACUGAAGAAUUGUGGCAAAGUAUUUUCAUACUCUUAACUAAUGAAAUAGUCAUUUUUAGUCUUCUUAGAUUUUAUUUAAAUAGACUUUGUUAUUUUUAAAUAUAGGAGAUCUCAACGACAUUGCAGCAAAACUAGAAAACAACUACUAACAUCAUUUUUACAUAACAUUUUUGAAAUUAUUUUUAUUUUUUUUCCUGUAGGUUAGGGUAAGUUUAAUGUCUUGUCCUACAUAUGCAAUUCCCAAAAUUAAGCCACAGAUCACUUCUUAAUUAUUAAUUAAACAGGAAACGGGAUAGUUGUACAUUUAAGUCCAAUAGCUAGUGAAUUAGUAGUUUUAAACACCAUCACCUUGUGAUCUCUUCUGCCCUGUCUUUUUGUAGUUCUAGGUUCAGUCUGUCUCAGUGUCUUCUACGUUCUAAAUAAUAAUAGGGAUGAAAACAAUUAACGUUGAUUGGCACAUAAUAUGGACCAGCACUGUGCUAAGUGCUUGACAUGCACCAUCUCAUUUAAUAAUCCCCACAGUAGCUUCGCAAAGAGGUUCUGUUAUUUCGGCUUUAUGGAUGAGGACACGGGCACAGUGAAGUUUGGAAGCAUGUACAGGGUCACUCAGUUGGGACUCAGUUGGAGCUCUGACUCCAACCCAGGGCUUUAUGUUAUCAGAGCUGAUUGACAUUCUUUAACCAAAAUCUGGGCUCAUUUAACAUUAGUGAGAUGGAAAGAUUUUUACUGUGAACUACCCAGUGAUUCUGUGUGCUUCAGUGGGUAGUACAGAUCAUUUGUGCUCACCUUCAGUGGGUAGGUGGGGUGAGGAGAAUGAAGCUAGGGCCCUUUGUACCAUGUCACAUUGGGAGUGCAGCCAGACGGGUGUCCUGAAGUGACUGAGUCCCUUGGGAUAGCACCAGCAGGCACAGGCAGUGUGGUGGGCGAUGGAUGGAUGCUGCCUCCCUUGGGCGGAUGGUUUCUUCUCCCAGCCCCUUUUUUGAGUCCUGCAAGAGGAAGAAAAAGCCAGCAGCAAUAUGCUUGGAUAGCUUUAACUUUGGAUCUGUGUUCAGUGAAAAUGCUGAGUCACUUUGAAUGACCUGUUCCCUUAUCAAUUUUCUCCUUUGGCUUUUGUGCCUUGUAAAUAGCAAAUAUUUAUUGAUGAGGAGAAUGAAGUUAGUUAACACCUUCCUCACCUGCUACUUUCAAUUCUUUUGGUUUUUACCCUGCUUUUCAGCUCUGCAAUCUUUUUCCUGGACCUUGGCCUUUUCAUCGUGUGCUGAUAGGGUAUGGUGAAUGAGUUAGAUUCCUGUCUAGCAGUGCUGAGGUUGUUCCAGGAGUGGAUUGGCUACUGGCACGCCAGGGAUUGAGUUGAGAGUCAGGGAUAGAAUCUACUUCUCUGGUUGCAUGUUAGAAUCACCUGGGCUGCUUGAGAAACACGUGGUGCCCCACACCCAUUUUUAUUUAAUUGAUCUGGAUUGGGGCCCUGGUAUUUGGUGUUUUUCAGUCUUCUUAGGUGAUUCCACUGUGUAGCCAAUGGUUUCAUUUAAAUAUUAAUAGCUUAAUUAGGAAGCUGGGUUUAUUUUGGGCUGUGGAGAUGGGGCUCAAAAGAUGCAGCAGCUCCCCCAUGGGCACUGCACUGGGCAGAUCGUGCAGACCCUUCCUGCUCGCCUAUGACAUAAUAGCCAAUUCUUGGUAGUGCUUCCCCUGUGCCACGCACUGUUUGAAGCACAGUGCAGCAUUAACUCAUUUAAUCCACACGAUAUCCUUAUGAGGCAGGCACUGUGAUUAUCCAUUUCGUAGAAAAAGAAAUUCCUACUUGUAGCCAUGAAGGACAUGUAGUAUGAAACUGACCCAUAAACCUAGGUUUUGGUUUUUCCUAGAUUUACAGUAUAGAAAACAUUUCAGAUCUUUGUGUUUUAGUAAUUUAGCCUCAAAUGUGAAUAUAUUUGUUUUUACAAAUGAAACUGAGACCUGUGCCAUGUCAUGUAGCUAGUGACUAUCAGUUAGCAUACAGAGUUGUAAAUUGGUAUUGUAAAUCAUUUAAAACACUACUUUUUUAUGGUUUUGACAUAGAUUUUACUUUAUGGUACAUUUUAUAUUUCAGGUUAUUUGAGAUGUACCUCAUUUUUAAGGGAAUCUUUUUUACUUAAAAUUGUAUUUUGUACUUUUUAAAAACAUAUGUACUAUGAUCUUUGAGUGCAUAUUAGAUCUUCACUGACUUGUGAUCUGACCUGCCUCUUCACAUUCUGGCUACUGUAACCCUCCAGGAUACUAAGCAAAACUAAUAGCAGCAUUUGAAGCAUGCUCAAGUCCUGCCAUUGUAAAACCCAAACUCCUUCAAACCCACAUGCAUUUCUAGUCUCCCCUUUAAUAGCCAACUUAUUGAACAAGUUGUCUUUGCCUGACAUAGUCUGUAUUUCUUCAUCACUCAUACAAUCCUCAGCCCACUUUGUUCUGGUCUCAGUUCUGUCAUUGCAGUCUUUGAGGUCAUGGAGUAACCUCCAUGUUGCUAAAUUCAGUAACUAUUUUUAAAGCAUUUAUUCCCCUAUUUAUUGGUACCUGCCUUGUGCUAGGUUUGUGCUGUUGUAGGUACAGGUCAAGUGUCCUUUAUCUGAAAAUCUGAAACCCAAAAUGCACCAAAAUCUGAAACUUUUUGAGUGCUGACAUGACACUUAGAGGAAAUGUUCAUUGUAGCAUUUCAGAUUUUUGGAUUAGGAAUGUUCAGCUGGUGAGUAUAAUACAAACAACAAAACCUGAAGAAAUCUGAAAUCUGAAAUGCUCUGGUCCCAAGCAUUUCUGAUAAGGGAUACUCCAAAAGAUAUUGGGAUAGAGUAGUGAAUAAAGCAAAAGGAAGUCCCUAUCCUCAUGGAACUUGGGCUCUAGGAAGAGUGACAAAGACAUAAAUAAAUAUUUAAUAUAAUGUCAGGAUCAUGAAAGACCUCCUGUUGUGUGACUCUGCUGAUAUAAAAUGUCUAGAAUAGGCAAAUCUAUAGAGACAGAAAGUAGAUUAGUGGUUGCCUAGAGCUGAAGAGGGGUGAAGGGAGAAAUGGGGAAUGACUGCUAAUAAAAAAUGUUUUAUUAUUAGAUUGUGGUGAUGUUUGCACAACUCUGAAUAUACUGAAACCAUUGAAUUUUACACUAUAAUGAGUGAAUUCCAUGCUAUGUGAAUUAUAUUUCAAAGCUUUUAAUAUCAGGAAGUGGUAAGUGCUAUGAAAAAAAUCUAAAUCCACUGGGAGAUGGAGGUACUGUUUUGCAUAAAGAAGUUAGAUGAGACAUCUCUGAUGAGGUGACAUUUAAAUAGAUAUUUCAGGAAAGAUAGCUGUUGGGCCUGUGAACGUCAAGGGUCAUGGAGGCUGAGGGGCACAGUAAAUGCAAAGGCCUUGAGGUAGGAAUUCACUUGAAUAUUCACGAAUUGUGUGGCUAGAAUGGAGUAGGCAAGGAUAAUGGAAUGGGAUGACUUAGGUCAGAUCACGUAGAGCCUUGUGAGGACUAGAAUUUUUUUUCUUUUAUGCUGCAAUAGCAAAUACAACAUCUCAGUGAUUCAAGUAAAAGGUUGUAAUGCAUCCUUUGUGGGUUGGAAUGGGUCUCUGCUCCACAUCGUUGACAUUCUCAUCCCUAGUCUAUCUGAAACCCAUGGAAAAGAGGGCAUGUGUUUCUAGAAGGAAGGAAACAAGGCAAAUCUAAAGAGUGGCUCCCAACCACAGUGCAGCCUUGGCUUUAACAAUUUUUGUUUUCUUUUCCCAUAUCACGUGGUACAAUUGACUUUUCAGGAGGCUGAGCCAUGUGACCCAUGGCUUGAAACACCCUUAAGCAUUCCCUGAUGAAUCCCAGUUAGAGAGGCAGAUCCCUAUACCUCAGUCGUGUUCUUGUUCUGUUCCAGAGACAUUUAGAUGAGUGCCAAGGUUAGAUGGUAACCUUUAAUUUUGUCCAAUUUUGUUUUGCUUUUUUGGCAAUAACAUGGUCACUAUUUUGCCCUUUCCUUCUGCCGCCUUUACAGGUUUAUUUCAUCAUUUUCAUCGUCACUUGAAAAGCAUUUGUUAAGAGCAUAAUACUGUUUAAAACUUUUAUAUCUGAGAGAAUUGUUCAGCUGUAGUUUAAUAAUAAAACACUUUGAUGAUGCUUUAGUGACCAGAAGAGCGAAUUGUGCUUAAAAAUAGAAAGUUAACACUGGUGUUAAAUCUUUUCUGUACCAUUAUUUCCCUGGGGGAAAAAUGGUGAAUUGUUUUAGAUUCAGCCAGUUUUAAAAUUUUUUUCUUUAAUAUUAAAUUACUUUAAGUGUGUGGUUGCUUGUUGACAGCUUUGGUUAGGAAACGUUGCUGCUUUUUUCCUAUUACAGAGUGUAAAGUUAGAUUGAUAUUUUUGCUUUUAUUGGAAAUAAUUUAGAAUGGAAGAAGUAGCCUUGGAUUGGGAGUUAGAAGAUAAGAGUUUUGCCCAGCUUGGCCAUAGCUAGCUCUCUGACUCCGCUCAAGCUAAUAAAAUGAGAAUUGGACAAAAGAACAUGAACCAUUGAGUGCCUCACUUGCUCAUCUCUCACAUGCAGUCCUGUUAGUUUUUCCUUACACUGCAAUCACAUUUUAUAUAGAGGUUGGUUCUAAAGUCCCUGUGUAAGGUGAAGAUCAUUGGUGUUAAAAAUACCACUGGAAACACUUGCAGAAGAUUCCUCUUUGGAAGCUGUCUCAGAAGAAUCCAGCACAGCCUAUUCCUUCCUCCAGCAUUGGAAUAGAUCUCUGGCUGUUUAUUUGAGCACCAGUUGAAGCAUCUGGCCUCGUCUUCAACUUCAGUUUAGGGACCAUGUUUUAUGAAAAUACAUCACUUUAAAUACUCGACUCAUACCGUAUUGUGAGAUGCACAAAAUCUGAUUGGCAUGUGGAAACUGAGACCAACAGAGUGACUAUUCAUGUGUCAUGUCUCGUGCUCAUUAAGUAGAAGGGAGGGUGGGCAGUUAGUGAGACAACUGAAAUUUCUUUUCAUCUCGCUUCUUCCUUUUUUAUUUUUUUUGACCAAAUGAGAAGAGUUGAAUUUGUGUAAGCUAAAUAUCUAUUUUCUGCAACUCCAGUGUACUCAGAAUCUCUCCUCUCCAUUUUUACAGCCAGUGUCUAACUUACGGCCCUAAUGCUUUCCCACCUCAGUCACUUCUAGUCAUCUCCAUAAAUGGCCACUCUAAAUUCAGAUCACCCAUCAUCUUUGCUGCACACUUGUCCUAGAGUGAUCUUUUUAAAUAACUCUCCUGAUCAGAACACCUCCAUGGCACCAAGACUCUCAAAGGAGUGCUUCUCAGACUUCCCACCAAUGUUUUCCUGUACAGAGUUUGGUGGAAUAAGUUGUUUCAGGGUCCUGGGAGCACAGCUUGAUGUGGGGAUUAUGUUUGUUUUCAUGUAAGACUGUCAUAUUAUUGCUGAUUAGAAUUGAUGCUGCUGGAAUGUGCCAUUCCUGUCAUUACGUUUGCAUGGUCUCUGGUGCCUGUGUUUGAGGUACAGAUCCUUAGGAGAUUAAAUCUAAACGCUCAAGCAGGAUUCACAAGUUCUUCAUUUUCUGAUCUUUGCCUUCCUGUUCAGUCUCCUCUUACCAUGACACUUCUCACAUUUGAAGAUCACUUGAAGUGCCCUGAAUGUAUUGAAUUUAAGCCUUUGGUGCCUUUGUAUCUGCGUUUAUUCAUUUGUUGAAUAUUUAUUGAGCACCUAAUAUGUGCCAGGUACUCUUCUAGGUAUUAAUAUUACGGGAUACAGCAAUGGGCAAGAUUUAAGUCUUGGCCCUUGUGGAGCUUACAUUCUAAUGGGAGAGGAUGAUGACAAAUAUAUAAUAUAAUGUCAGAUGGUAUUAAUGCUGUGAAGAAAAGCAAAGCAUGGUAAGAUGAUAGAGUGAAGAUGGGGCUCUGUUGGUCUGGCAAGGUUAUGUAAGGAGGUGAUUUUUAAGAAUUUUAUCCUUAAUUGACAAAUAAUUGUAUAUAUUUACGGAGUACAAUGUGAUGUUUUGAUACAUGCAUAAUUGUGGAGUGAUCAAAUCAGACUAAUUAACAUAUCCAUCAAAGGUGAUAUUAAAAUGGAAACCUGAUGAAGUAUGAGAGCAACCAUGUUAUUAUUAGGGGGAAGAGCGCUCAAGGUAAGGAGAACAGCACGUGCAAAGGCGCUGAGGUGGGAGUGUUCUUGGAGUGUUAAUGGAGCAGUAGGAAGCUCACUGUGGCUGAGUAGAAUGAACAAGGGGAAGAUGAGUAGAAGAUGAGAUUGGAGAGAUUAGCAGAUGCAGGGUGUACAAGGCCCUGAGCCCAUGAUAAGUUUUCUUUUGCUUUGAACAGCUUCCCCUUCCAUCUGUAACUAUUGGGUGAGGUGGAAUUAAUUUUAAUUUGUUCUACAUGCUGACCAGUUGCCCCUCUGUUUACUGAAUUAUUAUGUCUUCUCCAUUGAGUUUGAAAUGCCAUUUAAUUAUAUGUUGUGUAUGUGUAUUUAUACGUAUAUGUUUAUCAGCUCUCUGUCAUUGAUUUUUCUUCUUGCACACAUAGUAUAACAUUUUAAUUACUGUACCUUUAUACCAGGUCUUGGCAAACAAUGGCCCAUGGGGCAAAUCCAGCCCUACCACCUGGUUUUUAUAAAUAAAGCUUUAUUGGAAAGCAGCCAUACUUACGUAUUGUUUAUGGCUGCUUUUGAGCUACUAUGGCAGUGUAGUUGCAACAGAGACUGUAUGGGCCAGAAAUCCAGAAAUAUUUACAAUCUGGCCCUUCAUACAGAGUUUACCAGGCUCUGCUUUAUACUGUGUAUUGAUAUCUGAUAGGGCAAGUUCAUCCUCAUUCUUUUUCAACAAUUUCUUGGCAGGCCUAACAUGUUUAUUUCUCCAGAUGAACUUUAGAAUCAAUCUGCCAAGCUUGCCUGACUUCCUUCUUUUCCCCACCUCUUUUUGGGGUGGAGAACUGGGGAGCCAGCAGAAUAGGAAUUUUGAUUGCAUUAAUUUGUGGUUUAGUGAAGGGAGAAGUGAUUGCUUUACAACGUUGGGUCUUUCUAUUCCAGAAAUAUCUCUUUACGUGUAUAUCUUUCAGUAAACUUUAAUUGUUCAUUCUGAACAAUAAAAUCAUACAUAUUGGAGUUUAUUCCUAUAUGUAUUGUUGCUUUUUGUUGCCAUUAUAAUUGCGUUCUUGUCCCAGUUAUAUUUUGCAAGUGACUAUGGUAUAAAGGGAAGUUUUUGCUUUUUAUGUAUUUAAAUUCUGUUUCUAACCCUCUUAUGAGAGUAAACUAUUAGGACUGUUAAUUUUUGUUUCUUUUGAUUGAGAGUCAUUGUCUGAACUUACCAAUAAUUGUUUUAUUAAUGUUUAUGUCUCCCCCUGUAUUGUGUAGUUUUCUUACCUAGAGUAGUUUGGGGGAAUGGACUUUGACCCCCUCAAUGGCAUUCAUUUUUUUUUCUUUUGUGUAGGUCACAGCAAAUGGUAGUUAAAACAAGCAAAAAAAAAAAAAAAAAAAAAAAAAAACCCAGACAAGUUUAUGCCCAAUCAGCAGUUGUUGGUAGUUUUAAGAAAAUCCAGAAGAUAAUCUAGGCAAGCUAUUUAUCAAGCAGGCUGUGCCUUUGUAGAGCUGAUUGCUGGUUUUAAUACAGACUAUAGAGUUGCCAUGUCACACAGGAGAGUCAGACUCAGCACUGCUUUACUUUGGAGAGCCGUCUGAUCAUGGAAUGCAGUCAAAACCCAGCAUUUAUCCUUUGGAAUUGAAAUACGAGCAGAAGGAGAUUUUUAUCAAUCAGUGCUUUCCAGAAUACGUUCUCGGUAAAGCAUUUGAUCUUUACCCUUAACAUCUAGGCCUUAAGGAGGUGAAAUCUACUGUAGAUUUCAAGGGCUAUUACUUGCCAUGAGCAUUGAACAGAUGAACUGUAAAUCCAAUGUGUGUUAACCUUUGUGAAUCUAUCUUUUAAUGACAUUUUUGUCUUUUUUUUCUCCUGAAUUUGUGUCUUAACUUCUCCUUAUGUUGAUGAGACGAAAGAAAAAUUAUCCAUGUUACUGGUUUCAUUUCUUCCUUUUUCUUUUUUCUUUUUUUAGUUGAAGUGAUGAUGAUGUGGUAGCAAUAGGGAUUGGAUAUAGAAAUGGAUAAUUGGUGACAUAUAUUAUGUAUUUGUGAAAUGAACCUGUUUACUCUUGUUGCCUUUAGUAAAGUAAAACUUCAUACGUGGAACCUGAUUUUAAACAUAAUAUCUGUAUUUUUGUUCCUGUGUGUUGUGAUUAUCUGCAGUCAACAUUAUGAACAUCAGUUGCUGGUAUAUGAGUCGCAGUGCCAUUCUUGCAUUACUAUAAAGAAAUACCUGAGACUGGGUAAUUUAUAAAAGAAAAGAGGUUUAAUUGACUCACGGUUCUGCAGGCUUUACAGGAAGUAUGGUGCUGGCAUCUGCUUGGCUUCUAGAGAGUCUUACAAUCGUGGAGGAAGGUGAAUGGAGAGCAGGCACACCACAUGGCGAAAGCAGGAGCGAGAGAGAGAAAGGAUUUUCAGCUGAACUCUCAUCUCUCAACACUGGCAAAUAUUCAUAAGAUCUACCACACCCUUAAUAAGCUGAACCUAACAGAAGACAUUGGCCAAGACGAUCACCAAACAGGAAGUCUGCGGUCUUGCAGUUCUUCAGACUGCUUUAAUAAAGUGAUGCCACCAAGGAAAAAGAGAAGACCUGCCUCUGGAGAUGAUUUAUCUGCCAAGAAAAGUAGACAUGAUAGCAUGUAUAGAAAAUAUGAUUCGACUAGAAUAAAGACUGAAGAAGAAGCCUUUUCAAGUAAAAGGUGCUUGGAAUGGUUCUAUGAAUAUGCAGGAACUGAUGAUGUUGUAGGCCCUGAAGGCAUGGAGAAAUUUUGUGAAGACAUUGGUGUUGAACCAGAAAACGUAGUUAUGCUUGUCCUAGCUUGGAAAUUGGAUGCACAAAACAUGGGUUAUUUUACUCUACAGGAGUGGUUAAAAGGAAUGACUUCUCUCCAAUGUGAUACAACAGAAAAACUCAGAAAUACUUUGGAUUACUUAAGAUCAUUCUUAAAUGAUUCUACAAACUUUAAACUUAUUUACAGAUAUGCGUUUGACUUUGCACGGCAAUCAAAAUACAAAGUUAUUAAUAAAGACCAGUGGUGCAAUGUCCUAGAGUUUAGCAGAACAAUUAAUCUUGACCUCAGCAACUAUGAUGAAGAUGGAGCAUGGCCAGUUUUGUUGGACGAGUUUGUGGAGUGGUAUAAAGACAAACAGAUGUCCUAGGACUUUAUGCAUAGCAGCGAGAGAGUCACUGUUACCACAGUUUUGUCACCCAUUAGCCAUAAAUUGCUGUUUGUAUCAAAGCGCAUGCUGCUUCUCUUGCACUGUUUCCCUUUCGCAGGGACAUGUUGGUGUUUGCUAUUGAAUUGGCCAGCUCUGCUUGCUGUGUGGCAUUGUUCUCUUGGAAGGCUGCUUUGCAGUUUGUAUUUACACUACAGAUUGGUGAAUUUGCCAACGUCCUCACUGUGAUUAUGUGUAUAUUGCUGUUUAAAUUUUGUAUAUGUGUAUAAAAGGAAAAAGGUUCACCUAGAGAUUAUUUCUGAAAAAUGUAUUGUAAAAAUAAUUUUGUGGCAUUUCUAGUCCCUUUUUUUGAAUGAACCAAUUAUACUUUAUUUGGUCUCCUAUGUAGCAUUUCAGAAAACAAGAGAAAACUGUUACCAUGAACAAACAUUGCCAGAAUUAACCUUACUGUUUAAGAGGCCAACUUCUGGAAGGAGGUAGGAGUCAUAACUUUUUAGAGGCAUAUGCCAAAUAUCAUUUGGUAUACUUAACAAUAUUAGUGUUUUAAAAUGAUGAGUUAUAAUUAUUUGAACAUAUAGAUAUGUAACAUGCCACAAAUCAUUUCUACCAUGCAAGGUGUAUAAGUUGUUUAUUUUUUAGUGUUAAAACUAUAAUAGCUUGAAUAUAGGUACCAAUGAACAAAUUCAAAUUGCACCUCUUUUCUUAAAAGAAUGGGAUUUAAACUCUUAUAAACAUUCUUUAACUUUUUUGUUUGUUUGUUCUCUUUUUUUCCUUUUGCAUUCUUCUAGCCAGUGAUUGAUCUGCUAAUGCUUUCUUUGCCACUCUAAGUAAAAUUUAUUUCACCUCCUCAAUGAAAACCUCAUGGUUUUGCUGGCUGUUUAUAACUGCAUCGCACUUCUAGUUGUGGCUUGAAUUUUCAGUUAAGCUUUCAUGGUAUGUAAUUUUCCAGCCUUUUGAGAAAACAAGCAUACUAUAAGUGAGAGCUGUUUUGUUUUCCUUGUUUGUUUGUUUCAUGCUAGGCUUUUCCUGGCAGCAUGUCCAUUGCAGGCAGUGGACAAGAAACCACCAGCAUUGAGCUAACCCAGUACAUGCUAGGACCUGUCCUAGAGGGGCCACUUUUCAUUACCUGAGUUAUUUGUACAGAAGGGCAAUAGCCAUUAUUUUUGUGGAUGAGGAAACAAGAAUAAACAGAAUGGUAUUUUUAGGUUUGUAUUUUAUGUCUUUUUUUUUUUUUUUUUUUGCCAUUCUUGAGGAAAUAUAGAGAUGACAUGUUUUCACCCCAACUAUCUGGUGCUAUUGAAUGACUAAUUCAGUCCCUAAAGUUCUGUGAAAACACAAAAGUCUAAUGAUUUGAGUGAGUAAAAGGUAAUGGUGCAUUUGAACAAGUAAAUGCUGUCGUGGUCAGCAAGAUCCGUGAUUUGAACAUGUGAUGACUGGAAAAAGGUUUGGGUUAUUUGGAACUCUGGCUAAAACUUCUUUCGGGUGACAUGUGAUCGUUUAAAUGGCAUUAAGUGAAUAAAGCACACAGACAGUGCUACUCUUGACCACUAUUUUACCAUUUCUUUGCAAACAGUGUUCACAUUUUCAUAUUUUUUCCCUAACUAAACCACCAAAGAAAGAAAUUUUGUAUGUAUAUACAGUGUGUGUGUAUACAAAAUCAUGAUAUAGUAGAAUGCAACUACUUUCUUUUUCUACCAAACGAAAGGUUUUAUUUGCUGUGAAAUAAACCAGAAGUUUAAAAAACCCUGUAGUGAUUAAGCAUACUUAACCACUCCUUAUUUGUAGAUUCACUUUCAACCUUAAAAAUUAAUACCAGUUUGCAUAAACCAAUAUCUGAAAAGAACAGGAAAUGUUAAUGGCAAGCAACAGCUAUUAAUACUGAUGUGAUGGAUGCAUUUGUUUUGCAGUGGUGACUGGCCUAGGCAGGUUUGGAUCUGUGAAGAAUUGAUUCAUUUUCAAAAUUAUUCCAUAAAGUUAAAAAGUUACACUUUAAAGGCAACAGGUCAUACAGUUCUUUAAAUCUGAUCAACUGUAGCUUUAUUUAAAGCAAAUAUAAAUCAUAGAUGAAGUUAUUUUAAACACUAUGUUAGAAUAUAGAGAUUUUUAAAAAAUGCUGAUAAGCACAGUUAAUUCUAAAAUGAGAGGAUUGUUACAGGAGGGAGAUGUUACAGUUAAUCCACAAUCAACAUUUUGAUGGUAGGGAAAAAACUGCGUAAAAACUAUUGCAUUAUGUAUGAUAAGAAAGUAAGUAUUCCAAAGGGAUAAUCUUGCAUAUUAAGAAAACUCCAAAUAAUCUUUAAACUGCCUUGAAAAAUAAACCUCUUUGACUGCUGAGCGGCAGAGUGCUUACCCUUGAUUGUCUUGAUUUUAUAUAUUUAUUUCUAAGGGGAGAAAAAGGGGUCAGACAGAGUAAUAUGAUACAUUUUCUUAAAAACUUCUCUAAGUUGCACAAAACUGAACAAUCAUCAAGCACUUAUUUACUGGCUAAUGUUGAAUAAAUUAGGGUGCCUUCAUCUGGGUUUUCUUUAGUACCUAAGUCUACAACCCUUUCUCUUUUUCUAUUGUGUUUCGAACUCCACAUUGCAAUACUCUGUUGUCAUGGAAUACAACCUUUAGAUGUUUACUGCUGAAGUAGGUCAGAAAUUGUAUUAUUUGAUUUGCCUCAAACAUCCACUGUAAUGUUACAUGCACCUUUUUUGAAGCAUGAACUCUGAAUUAUGUUUUUAUAAAUCUGACUAGGCAAACCUAGAUUCUGGUUUCACAAUGGAUUUAUUUUCUCUCUCAGUCUCCAUUUUAACAGUGCUUUUGAAGUUUAUACAGAAAGCUUUAAAAGUUAGUUUGUGCCCUUGGUUUUUAUUCUUAAAACUGCUAAAAUACCUCUGUAAGCCUUAUCCUUUAUUCUUUCAUAUGUUGUAUAAUAAAUGUAUAGAUUUCAUUGACCAACUAAAAUGUUGGGUGUCUGUAAAUGAGACCAAAACGUGGGUUGCUUUUUUCAUAAAAUAAUUUCUAUUGGGGGUUACUGUUCAAUGACAGCAGGUAACCUAUAACUGUGAAUGCUUCGUGUCGUCAGUAUUUGCAUUACAUUCAUAAAAGUGUGCAAGUCCUGUGACUCCCAGCUUAACUGAAAUACUGUUAUGCCACCUAACUUGAGUACAGCAAACUGGUUUUAGGUUUCAAUGACAUUGAUGUAAAAUGAUAUCCCAUGAAUAAAAAGUAUUUGUGUUUGGUUUCAGAA